GCUUCCGAGACUCGCAGUCUACGCGAGCUGCCUGUUUUUUUCCUGCUUGGACGCGCAUGAGGGCCCCGUCCAUGGACCGCGCGGCCGUGGCGAGGGUGGGCGCGGUAGCGAGCGCCAGCGUGUGCGCCCUGGUGGCGGGGGUGGUGCUGGCUCAGUACAUAUUCACCUUGAAGAGGAAGACGGGGCGGAAGACCAAGAUCAUCGAGAUGAAGAUUGGAUAACCAAGAAAUGACUAAUCAAGAGUCUGCCGUACAUGUGAAAAUGUGUAGCAGAAACCAGCCUUCUUCGAAGUGGUCUUGGUGUGAUUCUCCUAUCCGUUAUCAAAAACUUGAAGCUGUGAUUUGCCUGAGAUGCCAGAAUUCCAGAAAAGUUCAGUUCGAAUCAAGAACCCUACAAGAGUAGAAGAAAUUAUCUGUGGUCUUAUCAAAGGAGGAGCUGCCAAACUUCAGAUAAUAACGGACUUUGAUAUGACACUCAGUAGAUUUUCAUAUAAAGGGAAAAGAUGCCCAACAUGUCAUAAUAUCAUUGACAACUGUAAGCUGGUUACAGAUGAAUGUAGAAAAAAGUUAUUGCAACUAAAGGAAAAAUAUUACGCUAUUGAAGUUGAUCCUGUUCUUACUGUAGAAGAGAAGUACCCUUAUAUGGUGGAAUGGUAUACUAAAUCACAUGGUUUGCUUGUUCAGCAAGCUUUACCAAAAGCUAAACUUAAAGAAAUUGUGGCAGAAUCUGACGUUAUGCUCAAAGAAGGAUAUGAGAAUUUCUUUGAUAAGCUCCAACAACAUAGCAUCCCCGUGUUCAUAUUUUCGGCUGGAAUCGGCGAUGUACUAGAGGAAGUUAUUCGUCAAGCUGGUGUUUAUCAUCCCAAUGUCAAAGUUGUGUCCAAUUUUAUGGAUUUUGAUGAAACUGGGGUGCUCAAAGGAUUUAAAGGAGAACUAAUUCAUGUAUUUAACAAACAUGAUGGUGCCUUGAGGAAUACAGAAUAUUUCAAUCAACUAAAAGACAAUAGUAACAUAAUUCUUCUGGGAGACUCCCAAGGAGACUUAAGAAUGGCAGAUGGAGUGGCCAAUGUUGAGCACAUUCUGAAAAUUGGAUAUCUAAAUGAUAGAGUGGAUGAGCUUUUAGAAAAGUACAUGGACUCUUAUGAUAUUGUUUUAGUACAAGAUGAAUCAUUAGAAGUAGCCAACUCUAUUUUACAGAAGAUUCUAUAAACAAGCAUUCUCCAAGAAGACCUCUCUCCUGUGGGUGCAAUUGAACUGUUCAUCCGUUCAUCUUGCUGAGAGACUUAUUUAUAAUAUAUCCUUACUCUCGAAGUGUUCCCUUUGUAUAACUGAAGUAUUUUCAGAUAUGGUGAAUGCAUUGACUGGAAGCUCCUUUUCUCCACCUCUCUCAACACACUCCUCACCGUAUCUUUUAACCCAUUUAAAAAAAAAAAAAAGCUAAAAUUAGAAAAAUAACUCCCUACUUUUCCAAAGUGAAUUUUGUAGUUUAAUGUUAUCAUGCAGCUUUUGAGGAGUCUUUUACACUGGGAAAGUUUGUAGAAAUUUUAAAAUAAGUUUUAUGAAAUGGUGAAAUAAUAUGCAUGAUUUUAAGUAUUGCCAUUUUUGUAAUUUGGGUUAUUAUGCUGAUGGUAUCACCAUCUCUUGAAAUUGUGUUAGGUUUGGUUAUUUUGUCUGGGGAAAAAAUAUUUACUGGAAAAGACUAGCAGUUAGUGUUGGAAAAACCUGGUGGUGUUUACAAUGUUGCUAAUCAUUACAAAACAUUCUAUAUUGAAGCACUGAUAAUAAAUAUGAAAUGCAAAACCUUUUUAAUUCUAUGGUCAAAACUA